ACAAACCCUCGUUGGCCCCACAGGAGCCAGCCUCUGGCUUCUCUCUGCAAUGGCCAUGUGCUGCAGACCCGGAGUGGGUAGUUAGUUGGUUAAUGCCAGUCUUCCUCCCCUGGACACUGAGUUCUGCUGACAGCCCCCGCCCAGCCAGAGCUCUGCUGUAUACCACCGGGAGUGGGGCUGGUGUGGAGCCUGGAGGUCGCCCGCUGCCCUCCUAGGGCUGCUCCAGACAGCAUUAAAACGCUGCAGGUCGCAGGUGAGACUAACAGCUGGGAGAGCUGCUCCAGGCAUUUAGGACCCUGACUGGGGCAGAUGAGUCAGCCCAGUGGGGGCAGGGCUCCUGGAACGAGGAUCUACAGUUGGAGUUGCCCCACUGUCAUGUCACCUGGAGAAAAACUGGACCCAAUUCCUGACAGCUUCAUUCUGCAACCACCAGUCUUCCACCCGGUGGUUCCUUAUGUCACGACGAUUUUUGGAGGCCUGCAUGCAGGCAAGAUGGUCAUGCUGCAAGGAGUGGUCCCUCUAGAUGCACACAGUAGGUUUCAGGUGGACUUCCAGUGUGGCUGCAGCCUGUGUCCCCGGCCAGAUAUCGCCUUCCACUUCAACCCUCGCUUCCAUACCACCAAGCCCCAUGUCAUCUGCAACACCCUGCAUGGUGGACGCUGGCAAAGGGAGGCCCGGUGGCCCCACCUGGCCCUGCGAAGAGGCUCCAGCUUCCUCAUCCUCUUUCUCUUCGGGAAUGAGGAAGUGAAGGUGAGUGUGAAUGGACAGCACUUUCUCCACUUCCGCUACCGGCUCCCACUGUCUCAUGUGGACACGCUGGGUAUAUUUGGUGACAUCCUGGUAGAGGCUGUUGGAUUCCUGAACAUCAAUCCAUUUGUGGAGGGCAGCAGAGAGUACCCAGCUGGACAUCCUUUCCUGCUGAUGAGCCCCAGGCUGGAGGUGCCCUGCUCACAUGCUCUUCCCCAGGGUCUCUCGCCUGGGCAGGUCAUCAUAGUACGGGGACUGGUCUUGCAAGAGCCGAAGCAUCACUGACCUCACUAAACCCUUGCCCUGCACACUGCCGAUCAUGCCUGUGAAUUCUGGGACAGGCAUGAAGCCCAGCACUCGAUGGCCUCGGCCUCCAAAGACAGGCAUGACUGAGUUGGAUUCCUGGUUUUGUCUCUUAUAAACAGUGCGGUCGUGGGCCAGUCACUAAACCUCUCUGAGUCUGAGUUUCCCUACCGGAAAAAGGUGAAUGAUAAUUCCAACCUGCUAGGGAAAAUGAAAAGUGCUCAGUGAUGGAACACUUCUUCCCACAAAACUUGGAGGCAUGAGACCGGGUUCAUAUUGUAGCUCAAAGUCACAAGGUUACUAGUGACAUAGUCAGCAAGUAACUGCUGUUUCCCAAGGGCCAUGAAUGCAUGUGUCCUCAGAGGCCAGACAGGUCUCAUAAAUAGUGAGGAAACCAGUUGGGAAGGUGGUAAAGGGGAAGGAGUAUCUCCAUACACCCAGUCAUGCCAGAUCUUCUGACUAUUUUUAAAGCAAAAAUAGAAGCCAUCUUUUAUAUAAACUCUCUCAAUUUUUGAAUAUUAUAUUAAAGUUGAAGAAUACUAUGGACCAGACAAAACAUUCCUAUACACCAGUUCAGCCGAGAUCCACCAACAUGAAGAUUUAGCACAGCACCUGGUAUUUAGCGAGGCUGCAACCAAUGCAGCUGCUGCUAUUUUGUGAAAGCAACUGAUGGCUUGAAUGGGGCAGAGAGAGUAAGAGAUGGAGGGCACAGGAUUCAUCUGCAGUGAAAAUCUAUCCCUCCUUCUUCACCUCAUCCCUUCCCUCCUCGUUAUUGAGUGGGAGUGUAUGACUGCAGCCUCAAAGAGCUUCAACAGAGCUUCACUGGGCAUCUGGUGAUUUGUGAUUAUUCAGUGAUCUAGUGGGCAUCUAGUGAUUCAUGAUUAUCCAGUGAUCUGGCGGGCUGAGCUGCAUGAAGGUGAGGUAGGGAGACACUGAGGCCUCCUCACCAGGAGUUCGCAGGCCAGAGGAAGACACAGUGUUGUCUGGCAGGACGGGGUAGGGGGAGCCAUAGUGGGGCUGGAGGCUCCACGCAGUCCACUCUCCAGGGUUCCUGCCUUCCAAGCUUCUUCCCAACAUUGGGCCCUGGCCACCUCCUUCCCAAAGUUGGAAACUUACGGGGCCUCCUCCUGUAAGGAUCUACCAAUAGCCCUUGAAAGGCCUGUCCAGGGCGGCCUUUUCCCCUACCUUACCUGCCUCUGCAUCCCAUCAGGAUGCCGCGCCUUCUCCAGCAUAGCUCUUCAAGAAGGAAACUUGGGAAGUUCCCAAGACAUAAAAAUAAUCUGGGCCGGGCGCGGUGGCUCAAGCCUGUAAUCCCAGCA